GCAGCAGGCGAUGGCGGCGGCGGUAGCUGCGGCGGGUCGGUUAGGCUGGUUGUUCGCCGCGCUCUGCCUGGGCAACGCCGCGGGGGAGGCCGCGCCGGGCCCGCGAGUGCUGGGCUUCUGCCUGGAGGAGGAUGGAGCGGCGGGCGCGGGUUGGGUACGCGGAGGGGCGGCGCGGGACACGCCGGACGCCACCUUCCUCCUGCGCCUCUUCGGCCCGGGCUUCGCCAACAGCUCUUGGUCCUGGGUGGCCCCGGAGGGGGCGGGCUGCCGGGAGGAGGCGGCCUCCCCCGCGGGCGAGUGGCGCGCGCUGCUGCGCUUGCGCCUGCGGGCCGAGGCCGUGCGCCCGCACUCGGCGCUGCUGGCGGUGCGCGUGGAGCCGGGUGGCGGGGCGGCUGAGGAGGCGGCGCCGCCCUGGGCUCUGGGCCUGGGGGCGGCCGGGCUGCUGGCGCUGGCAGCGCUGGCGCGAGGCCUGCAGCUGAGCGCGCUGGCGCUGGCGCCUGCCGAGGUGCAGGUGCUGCGCGAGAGCGGCUCGGAGGCGGAGCGUGCGGCGGCGCGGCGUUUGGAGCCCGCGCGGCGCUGGGCCGGCUGCGCCUUGGGCGCGCUGCUGCUGCUGGCCAGCCUGGCGCAGGCGGCGCUGGCGGUGCUGCUGUACCGCGCGGCCGGCCAGCGUGCGGUGCCCGCCGUGUUGGGCAGCGCGGGGCUCGUGUUCCUGGUGGGAGAGGUGGUGCCGGCCGCCGUGAGCGGGCGCUGGACGCUGGCGCUGGCGCCGCGAGCGCUCGGCCUCAGCCGCCUGGCCGUCCUGCUCACUCUGCCCGUCGCGCUGCCCGUGGGGCAGCUGCUGGAGCUGGCGGCGCGGCCCGGGCGGCUGCGGGAGCGGGUGCUGGAGCUGGCGCGCGGCGGCGGCGACCCCUACAGCGAUCUCAGCAAGGGCGUGCUGCGCUGCCGGACCGUGGAGGACGUGCUCACGCCCCUCGAAGACUGCUUCAUGCUGGACGCCAGCACCGUGCUGGACUUCGGCGUCCUGGCCAGCAUCAUGCAGAGCGGCCACACGCGCAUCCCGGUGUACGAGGAGGAGCGCUCCAACAUCGUGGACAUGCUCUACCUCAAGGACUUGGCCUUCGUGGAUCCCGAAGACUGCACGCCGCUCAGCACCAUCACUCGUUUCUACAACCAUCCGCUCCACUUCGUCUUCAACGACACCAAGCUGGACGCUGUCCUGGAGGAAUUCAAGCGAGGGAAGUCCCACCUGGCCAUCGUGCAGAAGGUGAACAACGAGGGUGAAGGCGACCCCUUCUACGAGGUCCUGGGCCUGGUCACCCUGGAGGACGUGAUCGAGGAGAUCAUCAGGUCCGAGAUCCUGGACGAGUCUGAAGACUACCGAGACACCGUGGUGAAGAGGAAGCCUGCUUCUCUGAUGGCCCCUCUGAAGCGGAAGGAGGAGUUCUCCUUGUUCAAGGUGUCUGAUGAUGAAUAUAAAGUAACAAUCUCGCCUCAGCUGCUCUUGGCCACCCAGCGCUUCCUGUCCCGAGAAGUGGAUGUAUUCAGCCCGCUGCGCAUCUCUGAGAAGGUCCUGCUGCACCUGUUGAAGCAUCCCAGUGUCAACCAGGAAGUGAGGUUUGACGAGAGCAACCGGCUGGCCACACACCACUACCUGUACCAGCGCAGCCAGCCGGUGGAUUACUUCAUUCUCAUCCUGCAGGGCAGGGUUGAAGUGGAGAUCGGGAAAGAGGGUCUGAAGUUUGAGAAUGGGGCCUUCACGUACUAUGGAGUGUCGGCCCUAACUGUGCCAUCCUCGGUUCACCAGUCCCCGGUGUCCUCGCUCCAGCCCAUCCGCCAUGACCUGCAGCCCGACCCAGGUGACGGCACGCAUUCAUCUGCGUAUUGUCCCGACUACACCGUGAGGGCGCUCUCUGAUCUGCAGCUCAUCAAGGUUACGCGACUGCAGUACCUCAAUGCACUCCUGGCUACCCGAGCCCAGAACCUGCCACAGUCCCCUGAGAACACCGACCUGCAGGUUAUUCCAGGCAGCCAGACCAGGCUCCUUGGUGAGAAGACCACCACAGCGGCAGGUGAGUGCCAAGUGGUACAUCGUGCAUGGUGUCUGGACCUGAGGGCCGUGAGCUCACACACACAGACUUGCACUCUCGCCGCCCCCCCACCCUCUGUCUUUUUUCUCUCUUUUCUCCCCAUCCUUUUCCCUUCUUUAUAUAUAUAUAUCUAUAUAUAAAUAAUUUUUUUUUUUUUUGAGAUGGAGUCUUACUCUGUUGCUCUGUUGCCCAGGCUGGAGUACAAUGGUGUGAUCUCGGCUCACUGCAACCUCCGGCUCCUGGGUUCAAGCAGUUCUCCUGUCUCAGACUCCUGAGUAGCUGGGAAUACAGGCGCCCACGACCACGCCUGGCCAAUUUUUGUAUUUUUAGUAGAGAUGGGGUUUCACCAUGUUGGCCAGGCUGGUCUUGAACUCCUGACCUCAGAUGAUCCGCCUGCCUCACCUUCCCAAAGUGCUGGGAUUACAGGCAUGAACCACUGUGCCCAACCCCCUUCUUGCUUUUUUUUUUUUUAAUUCAUUAUUCAACUUGAACUUCUUGCUGUCUUUAAUAGCAUGGAUGACACCAAACUAUAGACUAACUGGUAUUUAGAGUAGAGUAUAGUAAGUCGGUAUUUCUCUCAAGGACGUCUUAGAAUGGAUUGACUUAAUCAGAGAUUUGUUGGGAAGUGGGAAUAAGUUUUAGUUCAGACACUCUUUUGGCCAUUUAAGAUUAAGUUUAGGUCACUUUGAGUCAGCAGUGGCCCUGGCUUAGAGGGUGUGUGGCUGGCAGACACCAUCCUAGACACUAGAAGGGCAUUUGUGAAGAGUUUGGUCAGUUCAUACUAAUAUUUAAGCGUGGCCCAUCCAGUGCUCCACUGCGAGCAGGAAGAUUGUGUUGGAAGAAAUUUUGCAAAUCGAACUAAAGGUUGUGGGAUAUGGAACCCCAUCCCCACACUGCAAGGAGGGAGGUGAAAGAGUCUGAAGUGUAGGCUGUGGGUAGGAGUGGUGAAGGGUUUCUUGUUCUUGUUUUUCAAGAAGAUACUUUAAUUCUGAUUGCGUUCCUAAGGUUGGGGUCAGAGAUAUGCCUGAACUUGAGAUUCCUGGAAGAGCUGGUGGGGCUGUGGAGGGAGCUGCAGGCUUGCCUCCUCCCACCCCCACCUGCCCCACCACGAGGAAGACAAGCUGUUAUCAGCACUUCCUCUGCCAGGCACUGUGCUAGGAGCUUCCAUGUCUAACUCUGCUAACCUCCCCGUGGCCAGAGGGCUGCUAGCUGUUCUGCCUGUUCUACAGGGCAGGAAUGAGAGCCAGAGAGAAGGCCCAGGGACUCUGACCUGCUUCCUGUAGGCCUCCCGUGGAGCCACUGUGGCUGCUCAGACCCACACUCGAGAGCACAAACAUGUUUUUCUAAUAGUCCUUUCUGAAUUGUGAGGUCACAUGCAGGUGCAAGGGACAGAAAUCCCACCCUGGGCCAUGUGGAUGCUUCAGCCCCUGUGGGCUCCAGAUCUGGGUGUUGGCAAAAAGGCAGCGGGUGAGGUCGUGCUGCUUAAGUCUUGGAUCUGGGGAUGGGUUGCAUCUCUUCCUAAAGAGAUCUCUCUAAGGAUGGUGCUGCACUUUUUUUUAAGAGAUAAGGUCUUGCCAUGGUGCCCAGGCUGGCUUCAUACUCUGGGCUCAAGUGAUCCUCCUGCCUCAGCCUCCAAAGUAGCUGGACGAGUAGCUAGUGCCGCACCUUUUAGGGUUGUUGAGGCUUCUGUGCUUACCCACUGUGAUGGUUUCUUAUUGUAUGGGGUGCCCCUUCUACAGAAGUUCACAUUGUCACAUUACACUGGGGUCUCAGAGGCCAAGGUUUUAAAAAUGGGAGUCUUUUGGUUUUGGUUCUCCCACAUGUGAGCCUUUUUCUGGCUCACUGCUACUCAGACUGCACGUGUUGUAGUGAAGAUACAGACCUAAUCCCAAAAUAAUGCUCUUCCCAUCACUGCACACCCGGAGAUUUUUAAAUAAUCUUCACUGGGCCGUCCUGUAAGAGAAUAGUUGAUAGUGGCUUUGUGGGUCAUUUCCUCUUUGUAAUGGAUUAUUCUCUAGACACAAUGUUGGUUAUUUUCACUUAAGUACAACCUGACAGUUGCUUCAGUGAGGCUGGCCUGCUGUCUUUCUGUUUCUUGCCUGAACUCGGGUUGUCCUGCAUUUUGUCCCGUGAGCUUGGCACUUCACUGUCCGGAGGAGCGUAGGGCCGCUGCACACCUGGAGAUUUUGGUGGGGCACUGCUUAAAUCAUGCAGAUGAGAACCAGUUUCUGGAGACCUUGGCACUAGACGCCCAGCAGAGAAGUGCCUUUUUUGAGACUUGGAAGACACAAUAAUUUUAAAUUGCCUACAGCAGGGGUUGGCAAAUAGUGGUGCAAGGGCCACAUCUGGCUAGCAGCCUAUUUUUGAGAAUGAAGUUUUAUGAGAACCCACACAUCUGUUUGUAGAUUGCUAUGGCUGCCUUUGAGUUACAGCAGUGGAGCUGAGUAGCUGUGACAGAGACUAUAUGACCUACAAAAACUAAAAAUAUUGGUCCUUUACAGAAAAAGUUGUCUGACCCCUGGCCUACUAUUUCAAAUCCUGGGUAGGUCCUCCACGUCAGUUCUUCAUGGAACUGUAUUGCCGAGGGAAAGGCAGUCCCCACACUGUGCAGCCCUCCAUGCUGUGCUCCUGGCUUUCUCUGCCAUCCUGAGCCGCAGGCUGUGGGGCAGCGCAGCACCAGCACUGCAGCUGCCAGCUCUCCCUCAGCUUCCCCUGCCCGGGGCACCGGCCCUCUCCAUGGUGCUGCCCGGAGCCAAGAGGCACAACCAUUUCUGCUCAAUAGCUUCUCCUCUUCUUUCUCUCUCUGCUCUCUUUAGCCUUCCCAGUAGACCUUUCCCUCUUUGGCACAGUUGGAAACUGCAGUUGAUAAAUGACUGUGGACUAGUGCGCGUUUUUUGUUUUCAGAGCACACGUAAGGUAAAUAUCUUCCCUCUCCCUGCCCCUUCACUUCCCUUUCCUGGCCCUUCAGCUGAGGGAGGAGCAGAGCCCAUGGCUCCCCAGGCUGGGGGGCAUUUUUCUCCAGGGGUGUGGGGUGGGCGCUCCCUUCCAUCCUUCUGGAAGACAGGAGGGGUCAUGAGACUCCUCCACUGUGGAAAAUGGUGCUUCCUUCCAGCACAGGGUGCUGUAUCGUCCCGGGAAGGUGCCUCUUGUUCAGCAUAAUGACCUGGGACCCUCGGGGCCAGAAAUCCACAGCCCCAGCUUCCCCGUCUCCCAGGGAAGGCAUCUGUUGGCUGACCAUCUGCUAACCAGUCGCUCCUGUUUCUGCUCUGAUACUUCCCAAGGCAUCCCGAAGCACCUGUCUUAGCUGCCCCUUCCUGUCCCACAGAGGAUUUGGCACUUGGUUUUGACAGGAUACUUUACCAGCUUUGAUGUUAAUUCUCCUUCCCUUGUCUCCUGUAGGGUCCAGCCACAGCAGGCCCGGCGUCCCGGUGGAAGGCAGCCCUGGGCGGAACCCAGGCGUUUAACGGCUCACUAGGCAGCCCCAGAUCUGGGGAACAGAUGAGCACGUGGGGAGCUGGAGUGAGCUGAGCAGAAGUUUUGUGCCCGCCUGCCCCCAUCCCCUCCAGGCCACGUUUUAGAUGGCCCUUGUAGUUGCGGGUCCUGGGUGUCCUCAGAACUAGACAUCAAUGCCUGGAUCCUUCAGCCGGCCCUGCCCUCCUUUAGGAGACAGGAGUCACCAGGGCACAGCCCUCCAGGCCCGCCUCAGGAAGGAAUGAAAGGAAUGCCAUCAUCUCUAGUUCCCAGGGCCCAGCCUUCCCCUUCUCCCCCGGGGCAGGGACAGUGCGGCAUAUUCAGAUUCAGACCUCUUUGGGCUGAGCCACCUUGUGAGUGCAGUUACUGCCUUUGUGUGGCCGUGACCUCUAUUUGUUUGCUUUUAAUUUGCCAACCUAUCGCUGCUGGCAGCACUUUUUGAGCAAGCCGAGAGCACCCAUUUUGGCUGGGGGUUCAGAUCGAUGGCCUUGUCCAUGUUGUCCUUUCUGGCUUCCCUGAUGGUGUCAUGUUUCAGCGCAUGCGCCCCAGCCUUUCCCAUGUGCCAAACCAGAAGCUCCACUGCCCGUAGGCUGUCCCUGUAGCCCUGCUCCCUCCCUGGAGGCUGCUCUUCUGAUUCUGAGAGCUGGCCUAGUGGUGCUGAGGGCCCCUUUCUGCUUCUCUGCCCACCUGCUGAGUUGCCACUCGCAGUGUUGUCAGUUCCCGUGUUCUGAGAAGAGGUCAUGCCUGGGAGGAAGGGAUCGUCAUGCUGCAUCGAAUCCUCUCUCCGCCGUGUGGCCCCCAGGAGAGUAGCUGCCUGUUGCACCUGCUCCACACCUCCCCACAGCCUCCCUGCAGGUGCUGUGUGGCCGUGAUGUGCAGAGAGCAGUGAGGGAGGGUUCAUGAACCAGGUGGAUCCUCUUUAAAAAAAAAAAAGUUUUUGUUAUAUCUCUA